AGCAAUAGUGGAGGCAGGCUGAAAAUCAGUCCCAGCCAUACUCAGCUCAAAGAAAUUUUUCACAGAGAGCUCUUCAAAGCUCCUGUUCUCAGAGAAGCAUAAGAAAGGGACUGUUUUGUGCUCACAGUGUGUGUGGGCUUUAUGAAGAAAAAAAUUUGUGGCCUUAUGUGAACAGAGUAUGCUGUAUGCAGAUUUGGUGGGCAAAGCUACAAAAUGAAAUCUACUCAAGGGGCUCAUAUAAUCAUAUGGUCAAUUUCAUGUUGGAUCAACAAACAUUCAGGAGCCCAGUACUAUGUGCCAGGCUCUGAAUUAGAACUGGUGAGUAACAAGAAAAAUAAAGCAAAGUCCCUGCUAUGGAGGAAUUCAGUCUAAUGGGGAAGAUAGACAUCCAGGGCAAGAAGUGCUAUGCUUGAGCAAAAGUCAUCCGGGAAGGCAUUGUUUAACCUGAGUUGCAGCCAUCUAAAUCUUGCUGAAAAGGAAUAUUUUGGAUUAGAAUUCUGCAGCCAUUCUGGAAAUAAUGUUUGGCUGGAGCUUUUGAAGCCCAUAACAAAGCAGGUAAAAAAUCCUAAGGAGAUUGUUUUCAAAUUUAUGGUGAAAUUUUUCCCAGUGGACCCUGGACAUCUGCGGGAAGAACUUACAAGGUAUCUUUUUACUCUUCAAAUAAAGAAGGAUUUGGCUCUAGGAAGGCUUCCAUGCAGUGACAACUGUACAGCGUUGAUGGUAUCUCACAUCUUACAAUCAGAACUUGGAGACUUUCAUGAAGAAACAGAUAGGAAGCAUCUGGCACAAACUCGGUACUUACCAAACCAAGACUGUUUAGAGGGCAAGAUCAUGCACUUUCAUCAGAAGCACAUUGGCAGGAGCCCAGCUGAAUCUGACAUUCUGCUACUGGACAUAGCAAGGAAGCUGGAUAUGUAUGGCAUCAGGCCUCACCCCGCCAGUGAUGGUGAAGGGAUGCAGAUUCACCUGGCUGUUGCUCACAUGGGAGUACUGGUGUUACGGGGAAAUACAAAGAUCAAUACUUUUAACUGGGCUAAAAUCCGCAAGUUGAGUUUUAAGAGAAAGCAUUUUCUCAUCAAACUUCAUGCCAAUAUCUUGGUGUUGUGCAAGGAUACCUUGGAGUUCACCAUGGCCAGCCGAGAUGCCUGCAAGGCUUUCUGGAAGACUUGUGUGGAAUACCAUGCUUUCUUCAGGCUUUCGGAAGAGCCCAAAUCAAAGCCCAAAACCCUACUCUGCAGCAAGGGUUCCAGUUUCCGCUAUAGUGGACGAACCCAAAGGCAACUUUUGGAAUAUGGGAGAAAAGGGAGGCUGAAGAGCUUGCCAUUUGAAAGGAAACAUUACCCAUCUCAGUACCAUGAACGACAGUGCAGGUCCUCACCAGACCUCCUCUCUGAUGUGUCAAAACAAGUGGAAGAUUUGAGACUAGCAUAUGGUGGUGGCUACUACCAAAAUGUGAAUGGAGUGCACGCAUCUGAGCCAGUGCUGGAGAGUAGGAGGAGGAAUUCUGCAUUGGAGGUGACAUUUGCAACUGAGCUGGAGCAUUCCAAACCAGAGGCGGAUCCCACAUUGCUACAUCAGUCCCAAAGCAGUUCCUCUUUCCCUUUUAUUUAUAUGGACCCUGUCUUUAACACUGAGCCCAAUCCUAACCCUGAUCCCAGAGACAUUUUUUCAGAGAGGAGUUCUCUAAGCUCCUUCCAAACAAGCUGUAAGUUUUCUGGUAAUCACAUGAGCAUAUAUUCUGGCCUCACAAGCAAAGUGCGUCCAGCAAAGCAGCUAACUUACACGGAUGUGCCCUAUAUUCCUUGUACAGGUCAGCAGGUUGGUAUUAUGCCUCCCCAGGUCUUUUUUUAUGUGGACAAGCCACCCCAGGUGCCCAGAUGGUCCCCAAUUAGAGCAGAGGAAAGGACAAGUCCACAUAGCUAUGUAGAGCCCACUGCAAUGAAGCCAGCUGAAAGAAGCCCAAGGAAUAUCAGAAUGAAGAGCUUUCAGCAAGACCUGCAAGUACUCCAAGAAGCUAUAGCCAGGACUAGCGGUAGGAGCAACAUCAAUGUAGGUCUAGAAGAGGAAGACCCAAAUUUGGAAGAUGCAUUUGUAUGUAACAUUCAAGAGCAAACCCCUAAAAGGUCCCAGAGCCAAUCAGACAUGAAAACUAUUCGUUUUCCUUUUGGGUCAGAAUUUAGACCUUUAGGGCCUUGUCCUGCUCUCAGUCAUAAAGCAGACCUGUUUACGGAUAUGUUUGCAGAGCAGGAGUUGCCAGCAGUUCUAAUGGAUCAAAGUACAGCAGAAAGGUAUGUAGCUAGUGAAUCCAGUGAUUCUGAAUCAGAGAUUCUUAAACCAGACUACUAUGCUUUGUAUGGCAAAGAAAUAAGGUCACCCAUGGCCAGAAUCCGCCUGUCUUCUGGUAGUCUACAGUUAGAUGAAGAAGAUGAAGAUGCUUAUUUCAACACACCAACUGCUGAAGACAGGACUUCACUAAAACCAUGUAAUUACUUUUUAGCUUAAAAGUGUGAACCUAUGGACAUUUCUGAGCCAGUUCCAUGUUACCGACUUAGGCAGAAAAUAAUGAAGUUGUAGAAACCAUUUUCUUGGUUACUACAUAUUCAUUGGUAUUAAGGAAAUCUCAUUUUGGAUGCCUGCCUUAUGAAAGAUCCAGCUGUUGCCUCAUUCCUUGAGUUUCACUCUUCCAUUACCUCUGAAGGGACUUUAGAACAUGCCCUCUCCUCACCAGCACUGUGGCAAGGCAAGGUGGGUAUUUGUCAUCUCCACUGCAUACUUCCUCAUAGAGACAUUGUGAGUGAAGGUCAGGCUCUUCAAUGCUGAAGAAUGGUGACAGUAUGGGUUGGCAUAUGGAAUUAGCGUCUAAUGGCAUUUAGUGAUUUAGUAGAUUGUGACUGUGUUGAUCUUUGUGCUCUUAAACAACACUGAACAAAUAUUUCAGUCUUUACUAUUUGUGUGGGGCCCAGUAGAAAUGGUCUUGUAAUAUGCUAAAUACUUCCAUUUUUAUAACAUAUAAAAGCAGAGCAUGGCCCUCCUACAGCCUCAGGAAGGAGGUGGUGGCAUAGAUCCUCUCAAGAGAAUACAGGUUUAGAAUUAAUCUAGGACUUGGCAGAAUUCUAAACCUAGGAAAUUCAUGAAUUAAAUCAAUUUCUAGAGCCAGACAUAAACCAGAUGAAAGUAUCAUGUUGUUUUACUUAUAACUUCUAUAUUCUUAUCUACUAUAUCUAGUAAAAGAGAAACAUUAUCAGGUCAGUUUGUUUAUCUAAUAUUUCCUGCCAGAAUUUAUUUUUUGUCAUAGCUUCUUGCAUGUAUGCAGGCCAGGAAAUGAAUGUUAUUGUAAUAAAGUGUGAUGGAAAAUCCAGGUAAUUAAAAAAUAAAUUAUAACUA